CCAACAGAAUCCUGGAUUUGAGUCUGUCCUUUGAAAGCAUCUCUGCUAGAGUUCCCACUUCCAAACCCCUUUCAGCUCUUCGGGAUUCAGCCUCCAGGUUGCCCUCGGAGUGGAGUCUGUGGCUUUCCACCGGAGCAGCGCCCAGGAAGUGUUUUCGUGUGAUGAAAGUUAUUUUUCAGUGCUGUACAAGCGUCUUGAAUUACUCUGGUAGCUUUUCCAGAAAGACCCAUGACUUCACCACAUUUCUCGAGUUACGAUGAAGGUCCUCUGGAUGUCAGCAUGGCAGCCACAAACCUGGAGAACCAGCUGCACAGCGCACAGAAGAACCUCCUGUUCCUUCAGCGGGAGCAUGCCAGCACGCUCAAGGGGCUGCACUCCGAGAUCAGGCGGCUGCAGCAGCACUGCACAGAUUUAACAUAUGAGCUGACAGUCAAAAGUUCGGAACAGACAGGAGACGGGACUUCUAAAAGCAGUGAAUUAAAGAAAAGAUGUGAAGAGCUGGAAGCCCAACUGAAAGUGAAAGAGAACGAAAAUGCUGAGUUGUUGAAAGAACUGGAGCAGAAAAACGCGAUGAUCACAGUGCUGGAGAACACCAUCAAGGAGCGAGAGAAGAAGUACCUGGAGGAGCUGAAGGCCAAGAGUCACAAGCUGACCCUGCUGUCUAGCGAGCUGGAGCAGCGGGCCAGCACCAUCGCCUACCUGACCUCCCAGCUGCACGCCGCCAAGAAGAAGCUCAUGAGCUCCAGCGGGACCUCAGAUGCCAGCCCGUCAGGGAGCCCCGUGCUGGCCAGCUACAAGCCAGCGCCCCCCAAAGACAAGCUACCCGAAACGCCUCGCCGCCGCAUGAAAAAGAGCCUCUCAGCCCCCUUGCACCCGGAAUUUGAAGAGGUCUACAGAUUCGGGGCAGAGAGCAGGAAACUCCUUUUGCGGGAACCAGUGGAUGCUAUGCCCGACCCCACCCCAUUUCUGCUGGCUAGGGAGUCCGCCGAGGUCCACCUCAUCAAAGAGAGGCCCCUCGUCAUCCCCCCCAUCGCCUCCGACCGAAGCGGCGAGCAGCACAGCCCGGCCCGCGAAAAGCCGCACAAGGCCCACGUCGGGGUGGCACAUCGGAUCCACCACGCCACCCCGCCGCAGGCCCAGCCCGAGGUGAAGACCCUGGCGGUCGACCAGGUGAACGGAGGCAAGGUGGUGAGGAAGCACUCAGGGACGGACAGAACUGUGUGAAGCCCGCCGUGCCCCACCCCGCGCUGUCCAUGCACUGUGAGCACCACUGGGAAAUCUCAGCCACACCUUUUCUGUUUAAUCCCAUGCAUGCCAAACACUUUUCACACCUACCGACCCAUUCUCCUUCUGCUUCUCUUGCCCUCUUCUUCACACCAAAAUAUGAUCGUGUCCCUGCCGCAGAAUAUGUAUUUCCUAAUUGCUGUGGCCAAACGCCUGUGUGCCGAAUCGCUUGCUUCUGAUCCCGCUCCGUGUAACCUAAGUGCGCUGCAGGCAAAGCCCAGGCCACGGCUGCGUCACUACUGAUGUUCACGAUGCCACACAGUCACACACCUAAUUCAUUCUCAAGUCGGAGCAACACAUACCAACCUUGACCUUAUCCUCAAGCUCCAGGGCAGCCUGGCCGAGCAGCCCCUGCUCCCUCCUGGAGACCCUUGUCACCUCCCGAGCUCCUCCUGGAGACCCCUGUCACCUCCUGACCAACCUUUCCCAGGGCGGCACCGAUCACCGAGCAGCCGUGCGUGUAUCUCAAGGAACUAAAUAAGAUGACGCUACUCCUCAUAGCACCACAACCUGAAUGUGUGUUCAUAUUUUUUUGUUAGUUUUAUCCAAAAUGUUUAAGAUCCCAACAAACUUUAUUUUCUAAACCUGCCUUCCUUCUGUUUUGUGUCUUUUAUUAAACAAACACCUGAAGGAGGGCUAGGAGACUGCAGGAGGGAGAGCAAUCACAGGUCCCAGAAGCGACUCCGGCCUCCUCCCGGCCCAGAGCUAGUCCUUAGAAUGUGCUGCGCUCCUGAGCUUCUGUGGGAAGCUGCUUUUGCCUCUGAUGGCCCCUGCCCACUGUGCUGCCCGUGCUAGCCCCUCUCCUCCCUCAUGGAGUGAAGCCACCCCUCACCUCCAGGUGGCCAGCCAGGGCUCCAGGCCAGCCUCAUGGUGCACAGAGGGAAGGGGUGCCCAGUGACCACUGGUCCUGGAGGUUCUGUGUCCUUACCUGACCCCACACAGACCCAGGCAGGCUGGGGGUAGAAGCUCAUGCAGGAACUAAACACUAAGCUCAACAACUUCACAGUCGCCGUAGCAGGUCAGAGCCAAAGAAGCUAGGGCCAGAGAGUUCUGGAAGGGGGAGAAGUGGCUCCAGGUGACUGGUCACUUCUGCUCUGUGCCCGACAUCAUCAGCCCUUCUUGCCAAAAAGGAGCAUCUGCUGAAACAGACCUGGAUCAUCGAAAACACACCUUUGGAAAUUACAUUAGGAUUCUCACUUGUGCCAAUGCUAUGUAUGCCAGGCACUUUUGCCUAAUCAAGUGUUUUCUCUGAGAAGGAAAAGAAAACUCCACACAUCUUAAAAUACUCUCCAAUAUUUACUUUUUGAUUAUAUAAAUUCCUUUUAAAAAGUAGUAUUAAAAACAAAACCAUUCAGGUUAAUUUGUAUGGAAA